AGUAAGUUCCAGCGCAGCUAGACCGCGGGGUAGUCGGCGCGAGGCGGAGCUUGGCAGUUCCGUCCACUUCAGCCGCAGCGUCCCUCACCGGGUGUCUCGCCGCAGCCUCCGGAGAGGAACAGACCCUCACUCUCUCUGUCAGAAAAAUGUCUGCUCCAGCUCAGCCACCUGCUGAAGGGACAGAAGGGACUGCCCCAGGUGGGGGUCCCCCUGGCCCUCCUCCUAACAUGACCAGUAACAGACGACUACAGCAAACCCAGGCACAAGUGGAGGAGGUGGUGGACAUCAUACGUGUGAACGUGGACAAGGUCCUGGAGAGGGACCAGAAGCUGUCAGAGCUGGAUGACCGAGCUGAUGCCUUGCAGGCAGGAGCAUCACAAUUUGAGAGCAGUGCUGCCAAGCUAAAGAGGAAGUAUUGGUGGAAAAACUGCAAGAUGAUGAUCAUGCUGGGAGCCAUCUGUGCCAUCAUCGUGGUAGUUAUUGUAAGUAAGUAUCGCUGAAGUUGCUGGUGGGGUGAAGAGGUGGGAAGGUCCUGGAGUCUUCUCCCUGCCUGCCUGCCUGCCUGGGGAGUGGGGCUGCUCUGACUGAGGUAUGGAGACCGCUGCUAUGGGAUCGUCACCUGGUUCGGGACGGGGGAAGGGCAGAGACAAGGGAUUUCUUUGAUGGACAAGCCUUCCCCCUGCAACGCAUUGCAGGGAGAUGGCGCCUCCUGUUCUGAGGAAGUGGGGCUAUGCUGUGUGUCACUGGCUUGGGUUGGAGGGAGACCAUGGGGAUGGGGCACUUAACAAUGGAGAGACCUGAAUGUCUGGUAACUUGGUGUAAUUCACCCUCUUGUUUUCUCCUGUCUCUUUCUCUUUUCCGUCUGGGACUUCCUGAUUCCUGUGUCCAGUCUACUUUUUUACUUGAGAAUGUACCACCCCUUCCCUGUUGUCCAUUGCCAUCCACAUUCAUGUCCUCUGCCCUCUGUUUGCUCUCUCAACACACUUCCCCACCCACCGUCCUCCAUUCCAGCCCAGGCUUCUCCAUCACCCAUUCCUCCUUUUUCGUUGCGUUCAUUUGCACUCUGUCCCUCAACACUAGAAAUGCUGCUCGUGGCACAAUCUAAGUCAUUACCCGAAGAGCAACAGCUGGCGCCUCCUCCCUGCCUGCUUUUUCUGUACUCUCAAGUUCCCCCAAAGCCCCAAAGAGUUGGAGGCCAAGGGAAGGGGCAGGGAGGGGAGUGGCUGAGGCGAAGUACCCAUGAAGCUGCCCAGACUUGGGAGGAGAAGAGUAUCGGUGCCCAUGGUGACUUCUAGAAAACCUGGCCACUGGUAGGAGCUAGGGAGGGGCUGGGAAGAUGGCAGCUCACUCAGUACUGCCUGGUCAUGUGGAGCUUUCCUUCCUGGACCAGGCCUGAAGAGGGUCCUGGGGGUGGACCAAAGUCCAACUUGGUUUCAGUGCAGUACCCUUUUCGAAAGUAAAAACUUGUUUUUUGUAGUUAUUUCUAAUCUGUUCGUCCAGGAUUUUCCGUGUCUUUGGGGAUCUUACAACUUUACUUUGUUCUCCAGAGGCCUGGAGAACACUUAGGGAUUGUGAAAAUAGCAGGACUUGUUUCCAUCCUAGAAGCAGUCCCAUGUGCUUCUAGCUGGAAGGAGCUUUCUCUUCUUUACAUUUUCUACAGCAUUCUGUAUGAGGGCACCAAAUAAAUCCAUCUAGCUGGUAGUUUUAUCUAGCCAAAUAAUUUAACCUAGCUCCCAGUUAAUUGUUGGCAUAAAGAGAGAGAUUGCCUGUUAGUUAUAGAGAAACAGUGAGUCAAGUGCUUAAUUUGAAAGUAACAAGCUCAGAGGAAGCCACUCCUUGCCCUCGUUAAAGAGGGUCCUGUUCCUCUCUUCCUGUUGAUGAAGGAGCGUGAGGGUGUUAGCAGUGUGAGAUCUUUGGACACCCAUGGAAUCCUUUCCUCCACACCACCCGUGCACUUGCCAAAGACAGGGAUGAGGCAAGUGGUUCUUCCUGGGGCCCGGCCGAUCCUCAGGAUGCAGAGAAGUCAUGUAGACCCACCAGCCCCACCUUGGGGGGAGGCGUGCCAGCCUGUGUCAGGUGUGCUUGUGUAUUGCUGUGCUGUCAUGGGGCCCUCUCCUUGAGAGCCGCCUCUCUGUUCUUCCUGUAGUAUAUUCCCCUUUGAACCACCCUUUCCUGUCUGAAUUCUACUUUGCCUCCUUUCUCUUCCUCCUCUUUGCAUGGUUUGUGUGUAUAGACAGUGGAACCUGAGGAUGGGAUCUGCUCAGCCUAUCUUCGGGGCAAUUGCUGAGCUUCAGGAUGGGCUAUUAAUGUGGGAUAAGCCCAGGUGCAAGGGGAGGAGGGCAGGCUGGGAACAGAGCGGAGAAUGCCCAUGGCCCUUUAUUCCUUCUUCCCUCGGUCCACGAACAGGAAGAGGCUGAGGCCAUGCUGGGCAGGGUCUGGAUGCCCACUUUCCAUGCAGCAGCAUUUCAUUGCUCAAAACCAUCCUUCCUUUCCUUUCGCCCUUGUUUCCCACAUUCCCUUCGUCCUGCCCAAGGGCGGGACUGAAGAGCUGGAAGAAAGCAGUCAGUACCCUCCCAACGGCCCCCCUCGAAGGUCUCCACUCUCCUCUGGGCUCCUCCUUGCCUAAUGCAGGGGGUCACCGCUGGAGAAGAACCACCACUGUCCUCGAUGUGUCCCAAGCCUGGAGCGAAUCCGUCCUCUUGGCUCUCCCAGCCCUAUCACAGGAAUCAUUCCUGGGUUUCUGUCCCUCUGAGGCUCACCAGGUGUAGUUGGCCUUGUUCUUUGGGGGUAUUAGCCCUUCUACUUUCUUUCUCACCCACCCUGUACCCUCUUCUGUGUGUCUCUGCUAUCCCCCUUUCCUCCCACCACCCAUGUGCAUGAGCAAAUGUGCAACAAAACCCUGGGACUUUGCAGUCAAAUGAAGCUGAGCUUCCCACAUCCCGUUCUUCGGUUUGCCAUGAGACGAUGUGGGGUUUCCACUGUGUGUCUGUCAUCACCUCUUUGUCUUUUUUUCCUAACCCUGAUCUCAUACUUGUAUAGAGUAAUAACAACAGUUGUACUUCCACCAAAGGCAUGUGGCAUAUUUACCAAUGUCAUGUAUUCUGAACAAAGGCAAAAAAUACAAAUUCCUACCAUUAAA